AGCAAAGGGGUCUGUCUGAGUGGUGGUCAGAGAAUGGGUGGAGGACUUGGUCAACUCAGUGCUGCCUCUUAAGCCGAGGGAAAGGAGAGAGAAAACUUCAUCUGAAAAUAAGAAGCAAACCCAAGAGUUAAAAGCAAGAGGGCUUGAGAAGAGAGAAGAAUCAGUGAAAUAAUCUCUUGACUGGAAGACUGAAGAGGAGCUGUUGGAGGACAGGAAGAUGGUCUGCAGCAUUGUGUCUCCCACCCAACCUGGCACAGCCUUUGGCAGGAUUUCAGUUUUUCUGACUGUUACAUGAAAGGAUGAUUGCUCACAAACAGAAAAAGACAAAGAAAAAACGUGCUUGGGCAUCAGGUCAACUCUCUACUGAUAUUACAACUUCUGAAAUGGGGCUCAAGUCCUUAAGUUCCAACUCUAUUUUUGAUCCGGAUUACAUCAAGGAGUUGGUGAAUGAUAUCAGGAAGUUCUCCCACAUGUUACUAUAUUUGAAAGAAGCCAUAUUUUCAGACUGUUUUAAAGAAGUUAUUCAUAUACGUCUAGAGGAACUGCUCCGUGUUUUAAAGUCUAUAAUGAAUAAACAUCAGAACCUCAAUUCUGUUGAUCUUCAAAAUGCUGCAGAAAUGCUCACUGCAAAAGUGAAAGCUGUGAACUUCACAGAAGUUAAUGAAGAAAACAAAAACGAUCUCUUCCAGGAAGUGUUUUCUUCUAUUGAAACUUUGGCAUUUACCUUUGGAAAUAUCCUUACAAACUUCCUUAUGGGAGAUGUAGGCAAUGAUUCAUUAUUGCGACUGCCUGUUUCUCGAGAAACUAAGUCGUUUGAAAAUGUUUCUGUGGAAUCAGUGGACUCAUCCAGUGAAAAAGGAAAUUUUUCCCCUUUAGAACUAGACAACGUGCUGUUAAAGAACACUGACUCUAUCGAGCUGGCUUUGUCAUAUGCUAAAACUUGGUCAAAAUAUACUAAGAACAUAGUUUCAUGGGUUGAAAAAAAGCUUAACUUGGAAUUGGAGUCCACUAGAAAUAUGGUCAAGUUGGCAGAGGCAACUAGAACUAACAUUGGAAUUCAGGAGUUCAUGCCACUGCAGUCUCUGUUUACUAAUGCUCUUCUUAAUGAUAUAGAAAGCAGUCACCUUUUACAACAAACAAUUGCAGCUCUCCAGGCUAACAAAUUUGUGCAGCCUCUACUUGGAAGGAAAAAUGAAAUGGAAAAACAAAGGAAAGAAAUAAAAGAGCUUUGGAAACAGGAGCAAAAUAAAAUGCUUGAAGCAGAGAAUGCUCUCAAAAAGGCAAAAUUAUUAUGCAUGCAACGUCAAGAUGAAUAUGAGAAAGCAAAGUCUUCCAUGUUUCGUGCAGAAGAGGAGCAUCUGUCUUCAAGUGGCGGAUUAGCAAAAAAUCUCAACAAGCAACUAGAAAAAAAGCGAAGGUUGGAAGAGGAGGCUCUCCAAAAAGUAGAAGAAGCAAAUGAACUUUACAAAGUUUGUGUGACAAAUGUUGAAGAAAGAAGAAAUGAUCUAGAAAAUACCAAAAGAGAAAUUUUAGCACAACUCCGGACACUUGUUUUCCAGUGUGAUCUUACCCUUAAAGCUGUAACAGUUAACCUCUUCCACAUGCAGCAUCUGCAGGCUGCUUCCCUUGCAGACAGUUUACAGUCUCUCUGUGAUAGUGCCAAACUCUAUGACCCAGGCCAAGAGUACAGUGAAUUUGUCAAGGCCACAAAUUCAACUGAAGAAGAAAAAGUUGAUGGAAAUGUAAAUAAACAUUUAAAUAGUUCCCAACCUUCAGGAUUUGGACCUGCCAACUCUUUAGAGGAUGUUGUACGCCUUCCUGACAGUUCUAAUAAAAUUGAAGAGGACAGAUGCUCUAACAGUGCAGAUAUAACAGGUCCUUCCUUUAUAAGAUCAUGGACAUUUGGGAUGUUUAGUGAUUCUGAGAGCACUGGAGGGAGCAGCGAAUCUAGAUCUCUGGAUUCAGAAUCUAUAAGUCCAGGAGACUUUCAUCGAAAACUUCCACGAACACCAUCCAGUGGAACUAUGUCCUCUGCAGAUGAUCUAGAUGAAAGAGAGCCACCUUCCCCUUCAGAAACUGGACCCAAUUCCCUUGGAACAUUUAAGAAAACAUUGAUGUCAAAGGCAGCUCUCACACACAAGUUUCGCAAAUUGAGAUCCCCCACGAAAUGUAGGGAUUGUGAAGGCAUUGUAGUGUUCCAAGGUGUUGAAUGUGAAGAGUGUCUCCUUGUUUGUCAUCGAAAGUGUUUGGAAAAUUUAGUCAUUAUUUGUGGUCAUCAGAAACUUCCAGGAAAAAUACACUUAUUUGGAGCAGAAUUCACACAAGUUGCAAAAAAGGAACCAGAUGGUAUCCCUUUUAUACUCAAAAUAUGUGCCUCAGAGAUUGAAAAUAGAGCUUUGUGUCUACAGGGAAUUUAUCGUGUGUGUGGAAACAAAAUAAAAACUGAAAAAUUGUGUCAAGCUUUGGAAAAUGGAAUGCACUUGGUAGAUAUUUCAGAAUUUAGUUCACAUGAUAUCUGUGACGUCUUGAAAUUAUACCUUCGGCAGCUCCCAGAACCAUUUAUUUUAUUUCGAUUGUACAAGGAAUUUAUAGACCUUGCAAAAGAGAUCCAACAUGUAAAUGAAGAACAAGAGACAAAAAAGAAUAGUCUUGAAGACAAAAAAUGGCCAAAUAUGUGUAUAGAAAUAAACCGAAUUCUUCUAAAAAGCAAAGACCUUCUAAGACAAUUGCCAGCAUCAAAUUUUAACAGUCUUCAUUUCCUUAUAGUACAUCUAAAGCGGGUAGUAGAUCAUGCAGAAGAAAACAAGAUGAACUCCAAAAACUUGGGGGUGAUAUUUGGACCAAGUCUCAUUAGGCCAAGGCCCACAACUGCUCCUAUCACCAUCUCCUCCCUUGCAGAGUAUUCAAAUCAAGCACGCUUGGUAGAGUUUCUCAUUACUUACUCACAGAAGAUCUUCGAUGGGUCCCUACAACCACAAGAUGUUAUGUGUAGCAUAGGUGUUGUUGAUCAAGGCUGUUUUCCAAAGCCUCUGUUAUCACCAGAAGAAAGAGACAUUGAACGUUCCAUGAAGUCACUAUUUUUUUCUUCAAAGGAAGAUAUCCAUACUUCAGAGAGUGAAAGCAAAAUUUUUGAACGAGCUACAUCAUUUGAGGAAUCAGAACGCAAGCAAAAUGCGUUAGGAAAAUGUGAUGCAUGUCUCAGUGACAAAGCACAGUUGCUUCUAGACCAAGAGGCUGAAUCAGCAUCCCAAAAGAUAGAAGAUGGUAAAACCCCUAAGCCACUUUCUCUGAAAUCUGAUAGGUCAACAAACAAUGUGGAGAGGCAUACUCCAAGGACCAAGAUUAGACCUGUAAGUUUGCCUGUAGAUAGACUACUUCUUGCAAGUCCUCCUAAUGAGAGAAAUGGCAGAAAUAUGGGAAAUGUAAAUUUAGACAAGUUUUGCAAGAAUCCUGCCUUUGAAGGAGUUAAUAGAAAAGACGCUGCUACUACUGUUUGUUCCAAAUUUAAUGGCUUUGACCAGCAAACUCUACAGAAAAUUCAGGACAAACAGUAUGAACAAAACAGCCUAACUGCCAAGACUACAAUGAUCAUGCCCAGUGCACUCCAGGAAAAAGGAGUGACAACAAGCCUCCAGAUUAGUGGGGACCAUUCUAUCAAUGCCACUCAACCCAGUAAGCCAUAUGCAGAGCCAGUCAGGUCAGUGAGAGAGGCAUCUGAGAGACGGUCUUCAGAUUCCUACCCUCUCGCUCCUGUCAGAGCACCCAGAACACUGCAGCCUCAACAUUGGACAACAUUUUAUAAACCACAUGCUCCCAUCAUCAGUAUCAGGGGGAAUGAGGAGAAGCCAGCUUCACCCUCAGCAGCAGUGCCUCCUGGCACAGAUCACGAUCCCCACGGUCUCGUGGUGAAGUCAAUGCCAGACCCAGACAAAGCAUCAGCUUGUCCUGGGCAAGCAACUGGUCAACCUAAAGAAGACUCUGAGGAGCUUGGCUUGCCUGAUGUGAAUCCAAUGUGUCAGAGACCAAGGCUAAAACGAAUGCAACAGUUUGAAGACCUCGAAGGUGAAAUUCCACAAUUUGUGUAGGGAUGUCAAAUUUCAGGGUUUUUUUGUUGUUGUUGUGUUAUUUUGUGGUAUUGUGCUUGUUUUGUGAAAGAAUGUUUUGACAGGGCCUCUUUUGUAUAGGACUGCCAAAUCAUGGGUUUUGCCUUUUGUUGUUGUAUUUAUCCUCUGUUGGUAAUACUGAAUGGUAGAAUGUUUUGAUAGGGUCACAUUUGUGCCUCACUGGAAUUAUCUUUAAAUUCUGUAUUUUUAAAGUUGUGAAUAAGAUAGGUGGAUUCGUAUUUUUUAAAGUUCAGUUGACUUUCCCCACCAAAUGGUCCAUUUGAAUGCAUCCCUAAUAUAUGAUAUAGUCUCAACUAAUAGGUGCAAUUUGGGAAAAUCAGGUUUAUUUUUUGGAGUGGAACUGUUAUAAGUGCUUAUUUAUAAAAGGAAUGUUUCUGAAUGCAAGUGCCUAAAAAGAUCUUUGUUGGUAUGCAUAUGUUUUGUCACACAAUUUUAUAGUGCAUCUUUCACCAUUUGUGCUUUUUUAAGAUACGUAUGUAAGCUCUUAUUUUUCAAUUGGCAAUUCAGUUAAUUUUUAAAUGUUUACAUAAUGGCCAGAAGGCUUGCAAAUCUGUAUUUAAUUGCAUUUUAAUUAAUUGCCAGUUUUUACAUGUGAUAGUCAGUUGUACAAAGAAAAUGCACUUAAACCUGUUUCUAAAUUAUAUAUUCAGUUAUAUUAUAUUUGGCUUUAGAUGGUUUUAAUACAUUUGAUAGUUUUUCACCCCUUGGCUUUAUUUUAUAUAAACUUUUGUUUUUCAGCAGUUCUGAACUUUUUAGUAUUUUAUAAAUGGUCCAAAAAAUGCCUGUUUCAGAAGUUUUUGAAUUCAGUGCAUUUCCUCUUGAUUUGUCUGGGUUAAAACCAUUCCUUUUGUAUGAAAUGUUUUGACUUAGGAAUCAUUUUAUGUACUUGUUCUACCUGGAUUGUCAACAACUGAAAGUACAUAUUUCAUCCAAAUCAAGCUAAAAUUUAUUUAAGUUGAUUCUGAGAGUACAGGUCAGUAAGCCUCAUUAUUUGGAAUUUGAGAGAAGGUAUAGGUGAUCGGAUCUGUUUCAUUUAUAAAAGGUCCAGUUUUUAGGACUAGUACAUUCCUGUUAUUUUCUGGGUUUUAUCAUUUUGCCUAAAAUAGGAUAUAAAAGGGACAAAAAAUAAGUAGACUGUUUUUAUGUGUGAAUUAUAUUUCUACUAAAUGUUUUUGUAUGACUGUGUUAUACUUGAUAAUAUAUAUAUAUAUAUAUAUCAACUUGUUAAAUUAUUUCAUGUUCCCGUGGCUUCUUUUCAGUUGUUGCCUAUUACAGUAUGAGAGUUUAAGGUUAUUAACCAUUGGCUUAGAAGUCAACACCUAGGAUCAUACAUCCGUUGACUACAAUGUGGAAUGAAUUUUAUGGAAACCUGUUUUAUAGUUCUAUGUGAUGUAAAGGUCUAGGGAGCAAUAACCAGCCCUUUUUUUUCUGAAGGCUUGUUUUUAGUCCUCAUUGUACAAAAUAUAAAAUAAUCAUAUUGCUAUGAAUACCUAAAAAGAAAAUUAGAGCCCAUGUGUAUUGAGCCUUCUCUGUGUGCCAGGAACUUUGCCAAGGUGCUACAUAGAUUAUUUUAUUUCAAGUUCACAGCAACCUAUAAUGGGUGGGUAAGCAUGUUAUUAUUUCUGUGUUACAGAUAAGGAAACUAAGGCUUAGUUAAAUGACUUGCUUCAGUGUUCCACAGGUGUAACAGGUGGAGUCAAAUCUCAAACAUAGGGCUGUCAGAUUUUGAUGGUUAGUGCUCUUAAUGACUGUGAUUACUAAAUAAUAUCUGGUAGUUUUUAACAAUAGAAAAUGCAACUUUAAAAAAUUUUUAUUGUGGUAAAAUACACAUAACAUUUACCAUUUUUAAGUAUAUUGUUUGAACCAUUUUUAAGCAUAUAGUUCAGUGGCAUUAAGUAUAUUCACAUUGUUUUGCAACCAUGAGCACCUAUUCAUCUCCAGAACAUUAUCAUCAUCCUAUACUAAAACUUAGAAAAUGUACUUUUAAACUUCUUCAGUUCUCUUUUAAUAUAUGGAGCCCACCCAAAGGUUAUAUCAUGUAAUAAACUCAUUUCUCUGUUUUCCCUCACAGCUUAAAAAUGAGAAUUUCACUUUUGGGUCCUUUCUGCCUUUAGGGCUCCCUGGCACUUUGUCCAGCGUAGAGCCUUAAGCCUCUAGAUGCUUUCUAGUUUCCUGGGGCCCUGAGGCAAGUAUCUCUUGAGAAGAGGUUGCUAUUUCUAGAGGAUCCACAGUGUGCACUGUGUUGUGCUAUCUAAUAGUGUGGUGGAAAUCAUUUAUCCAGAAGUUGUUUUUUGCAACAUGGAAAGAUACGUGACCAAAAGGAAAGGGCAACAGCAGGAGCCCUGUUAGUGCUGCCAGAACACCAGGAAGCCUUGUGGGAGGCGUAUUGUCCAAGAUGAUGCGUAUUGUCCAAACGACUCAGAAGAAGUCAUUUCUGAAGGGUUGAUCAUAACUUCCCUAGCCAUGUUUUACCUACAGAGAACUUAGUUAGAAUUUAUGAGUACAGUAUGUUAAAUUACUUUUAGUGUACCUUAGGCAGUGUAUUUGUUUUGAUACAGAGACAAAGACUAUAUGAUCCCUGAGACUUGUUGCCUAGUGAACUCACAAGCAGAUAGAAUUGUACCUCAGUUAUUUGGGUGAUUUAAAGAUGGUACUAUGGCUACACUAUUCCCAGCUAUCGUUGUGUUACAGUAUUUAUACAACUGGAAACAUCUCUCUAAAUGACAACCAUUGUAUAUUGUUAAAUAACUUAUAGUCAGUGGAAUUCUGUGGGUUUUUCUUUCCUACAGGCAGGAAAUUAUGGUGAUGUGUUGAUAUGAUUAUAUAUGUAGACUAUUCAGUUAACAUCUAGGAGUUAGCAAAUUUGCUACAUUCACAAUCAGUAUGUAAGUCAGUUGUAUUCCUAGAUAUCAGCAACUAACAGAAAUGGAAGUUUUUAGAAAGAUCUCUUCAAUAUCAUUAAAAAAUACAAAAUACUCUACCUAAGAAUAAGUCUAACAAAAGAUGUACAAGAUCUUGAUGGAGAAAAUGUUAGACCAUGUCAGGAAGCAUUUAAGGAGAUCUUAAAUAAAUGUAGUACUCCAUAAUGUACACGAAUUAGAAGACUCAGUCGUGUAAAGAUGUUCAUUUACAUUUGUAGAUUCAAUGUAAUCCCAACCAAAAUAUUUUUUGCAUUAUUACCUCUAUCUACUGUGUGUUUCCUUAAGACAAGGGCAUUCCUACGUAACCAUAGUACAACCAUCAAACUUAGGAGAUUGACAUUGACAUCAUGAUAUCUAAUCCAUAGACCACAUUCAAUCUGCUGAUUUUGAUUGCCUCAGUAAUGUUCCUGUGUUUCAGCAUCCCAAUCCAGGACCACAUAGUGCAUUUAGUUGCCCUAUCUCUUGUUUCAUUCAGUCCAGAACAUCUUUUCAGACUUGUCUUUGACCUUGACACUUGAGGAGGAUUGGCCAGUUUGUAGAAAGUUCCUCAGUUUUGGUUUAUCAUUAGAUAAGACCCAUAAGGUUUAGGAUAGACAUUUUUGUCCAAUACUACAGAAAUGAUGCUCUAUACUCAAAUGUGUCAUGCCAGGAUGCACACAAUGUCAAUUUGUCUUAUACCUGAUAGUAUUAAUUUUGGUCACUUGGUUCAGAUAGUAUAUACCAGGUUUCUCCAUUGUAAAAUUAGAAUUAGGAAGUAAUUUGUGAGGAGAUUCUUAAAGAUUGUAAAUGUAUUGUUUCUCAUCGAAUUGUCACGGGCUAGUCUAUUGACAAUUCUUGACUGAACCAAUUACUAUUUUGGUUGUCAAAUGGUGAGUCCGUGGCUUCUGCCUUGGUUGGCAUCCUACUACUGUAAGGAAGAGCUCUUCCUUCUCUAUUCCUUCAUUCACUUAAAUCAGUAUAGAUUCAUGAAUGCCUGCUUUAUUCAGUGACAGUGUAUUAUUGUCACUUAUUUUCAUGCUGAAAUUUUCCCCGAUUUGGUUUUUGGGAGUCUCUUCAAGCUGGCUUCUGUGUUCCUUAGAGAUGCCUCAUUGCUUUUUCCCCUCUUAUUUUUUUUACGAGCUCAUCUUACACUUUUUCCUACUCCCUACCCCAAGUCUAGAAUUAGCCCUUUUUUCCAAGGAGCCCUGGUUUCUUUAAAUGGGAAAUGGUAUAUGGAAAUGAAGACCUGAGAAAGGCUCACUGUCUUAUUGGUGAACAGCUCAAAGGAAAACGUGUGUCUACACACAUUCAAGAAUAGUCACCUACUUCUAUAUCUAUUUAUAUACAUACGUAUUGAAAACUUUGAGUUCACAUUGACACCUUCAAUUCAAUCCUUUGAGGUUAAUCUAGUCUCCCUUUCCAUCUUUGUAACUUCCUUCUCUCAUAGAAACCUGACUCCCAUAAUCCUAAAUAAUUUGUUCAUUCUUCCUCCCUCCCUCAACCUCUUGACAUGCCAGCUGCUGUCUCAUCACACCCAGUCCCAAAUAUGCCAAAUAAAUCCGCAGUCAUAGCAGCGCUGGUCCUGACCACACCAAUCCCUAACAUCCUCCCCAGCCUGGAGCCUGGACCAUGGCAGCUGAAUCUUUGACCCCAGUGAUGUCAGUCCUGAGCACACCAUUGGAAUCCUAGGCUCCUGUCAUCUGGCUGGAAGAGAGACAAAUUCACAACCUUUUGAUAAUGAGCAAUUAUUGAAUACUCACUGAAUUUAUCAGAGAAAGUUUAAAAGUGUACGAUUAUACAUAUUUACCAGGAAUGUUUAAACAUAGACAUUUAUGAAAUUUAUAGAAAAUAUUGAAUUGUGGUUCUCACUUUUUGGUCUUGGCUGUAACAAUUUUUAAAUAUUAAUACUUCCUACAAUAACUGUAUCAUGCUAUUUUUAAGUGUCCUCACACUCAACCAAUCUACUCUGCAUCCAUAAAAUAAGCAUGCAGUUCAGAAAAUAGAUUAAACGACUAAUUGGCUAUG